GUCAAAUAUAUUCUACACACAUCACAGCACAUUAGGCUUCGUAUUGUUCCCUCAUUUCCUGAGGACUAUUUCCAAAGAUAGGUAUGGAUGAAAUCAGAGAACGUUGGGACUCUAUAGGUCUCAGACUGGCCAGAAAAGAAUCAACAUAAUCUGAUGUGGGCUGUCCUGGAAAUCAGGAAACUCAAGAGGCAGUCAUCCCUACAUACAUUUUAGUAAAUUAUUUAACAUUUCUGUGUAUUCGUUUACCCAUUUGAAGAAAGGGAGCUAGUAUGUCUAGUCUUCAACUCUGCAUAUAGGAUGCUAUAAAGUAGUUAAGUUACAACCUUGUUCUUCUAACAUUUCAGCUGCUUCAUUUGCCUACAUCAAAAAGCACUGUGUAUAAAUCAUUGAAAAAAGAAUAUGUAUAAAUCCUUAAAAGAGCAGUAAGUGAAGUAAUGCAUUUAAAUUGAGAAUCAAGAUGUACAAAUAUAUAUAGAUAUAUACAAAUAUUUGAAUGAGCAAAACAUAUAAAUCUUUGAAAGAGGUAUUAAUGAAUUUUGAUGUAUUUUUAUAAACUGAAAAUUUUUGCACAAAUGUUGUCAUCAUCAUACUCAUAUUCUAUCCUAGACUAUUCUAGACUAGCCAGGUCUAUCCAUAUUCAUCAUUCCAUAUUCUAAAUAGCUCAGGAUUUUCUUUCUAAAAAUGGGACCAGGGACAGUCAUAUUGUGGGAAAUUUUUCAUUAAACAUCCCACGUUUCGUUAAAUGUUUUUUCUUAAAGCUGUUUCAAUUUUCAGCUUAUCCUAUUGAGGAUAACAAUUCUGAAAACUUAACAACUGGUGUUAAGUUUAAUAAUAAUAUUUGCAUACCAAACAUAGUACUUUUCUGUGUAAGAAAAAGUUUCACUGGUUCUAGGAUACCAAAAUACUGCAAAUUGAUUUCUGUUUUCCAUAUCCACACCCACCUUCCUGCUUUUGAUAUCUGUCUGGUAUUUUGCAAGACAGAAUGUUAUGUGAGAGUGAGCACCAAGCAAUGAUAUUUCUCUGCAGCCCAAAGAGUCUACAAUUUCCUCAAAAUGUGAGUAAUUUCAAAUUUAUGGUAUUGCCAGUUCUGCUUUUAUACUGGUAUAAUGCAAUGAAGUACUCAUUCAGAUUUUUAUUCUCUGUUGGUUUGAAGAAAACAUUUAGAAAUUCUUAAAUGAAUCAAUCGAUAUGUAGUCAAGGCACCAUGGUAGCUUCUGGGGAGAUCAUGUGAUUAUAUUUCUGUAUCUAGGAUGCUUGCAGUCUGGUUAGAAAGACUAGCCACAUUGUGAGAAAUGCUUUACAACAUGACACACGAGGUAGUAUCUGGUAAGGGAUCCUCUAGGUAGGUAGAGAGUGGAGAUUCAGAGGGCUUCCUGGGGCUCCAGGGGUGUGAAAGGCCUUGGGGGAAGAGAGGGAAUCUCUGCAGGAUCUCACCAAUUGUUUUCAGAAGAAAAUUAAUUAGAAAACACUCUUACGUAUAAUUGCUGUUCUAGAAAAUGGUUACAAUUUACUUCUUUAAAUGUUUAACAACAUUUUAAAUUAUGUAUUGUUUUCUUUUUGCCAUUCAUUCAUCUCUUGGUGGUUUGGGGUGUGAUUUGUGUUUUUCCCCUCUCUUGACUUAUCUGAGAAAUUCUGGCACUAGCCAGGUUUGGGAUGUUUUUGUUCAGACAUUCUUAAGUUAUUUGGUAAGAAGAAAGGCUUUGUUGCAUUUUUCUGCUGAGAAACAACUUUCUUUUUCUUUGUUUCAACCCUGAACUUCCUAAAAGCUCUUUAUUUCUAUAGAUUGUUCUACAAAGCUAUGCCUCAGGAGGUGAGAGACUAGGGAGCAUUUUUUUUUUGUUCAACUAGAAGUAGCCACAUUUUCAGAAAACAACUAAUAAGUUUAAAAUAUGUCAAAGAUAACUUUACAAGAGACCGCGUGAACAUAGAUAUGUAAAGGAGAGCCUAGUGCUCUCAAUGCCCAUAUCUGCAGGCCUCAAAAUUGCUUAUGAAGUCUAGAAACCAUGGCCAUCUGCCAGCCGGAGGCAGCAUCACCACAAUGGAAUUCACAGUCACUCUGUUAAGACUUUAUAAAUACAGUGAGGGUCCAGGAGCCAGGACCUUCAGGCGCAUGAGGCUUGUCUGGUCUGGUCUGGCCGACUGAGCAAGGAAACCCUGUCCUUGAAUGAGGACUUCCUCAGCUUCAGUGACUAAAUGUUUGUUCUCAAAAGUAAAAUGUCCCAAUGGAAGGUGGACAGCGGCCAUCUUCUUAUUUUAUUUGUUUAUUUUUAGCCAGGCACUCCAUUAGUUGUGGCAGGAAGUCAUCCUGAGAGGAAAGUCAAGGUGUAUGUACAUGGUUGACUUGGGGAAAGUGUUUGGAAGUUGGAAAAGUGGAACCAUUUUUGAGUGUGACUUCAUUUCUCUUCUGACCUAGCUCUACACAGUGUCAUAUCCUAGGAACUGGGUGCUAGCAUGAAGGAGAAAAGCAAGAUAAAUUAAAGAGCUUUACCUCUAGAUAGUAAUAGGAAACCAAGAAUCCAGCCUGGUGAUGGCUGGAGGGAGUGAUUGAAGUUAGCUGAUGCCAUGGGGAGUUAGCCAGGCAGCAAAAAUGUCUGGAAACCCGAUGUGGCCAAGACUGGGCUGUCCAGAAGCUCAUCAGAGAUAGACUCAAUCAGUACUUUCUCUCCCACCUUCCUGAACAAGAAGAAAAAAAUAUGAGAGAAUUGAGUUUGUAGUGUUCCCUUUUUCUCCCCCCAGGCUGGAGUGCAGUGGCACUGUUUCAGCUCACUCCAGGCUCAGCCUCCCAGGUUCAAGUGAUCCUUCCACCUCAGCCCCCCGAGUGGCUGGGACUACAGGUGUGCACCACCACGCUCCACUAUUUUUGUAGUUUUUGUAGAGACAGGGGUCUCACUUUGUUGGCCAGGCCGGUCUCAAACUUCUGGGCUGAAGCGAUCUGCUUGCCUUGGCCUCCCAAAAUGCUGGGAUUACGGGCAUGAGCCACUGCACCUGGCCGAGUUUGUAAUGAUUUCAUUCGAUGGCGACAGAGACAUAAAUAAUAACAGCAGCAACAACAAUAAACACUUGUUCUCUGCCAGGUGUUAAGCAAAACACAUUGUAUGCCUUUUCUCAUUUAAACUUACAACAACCAUAUAAGGAAACUACUAUUAUUAUUAUUUCCAUUUUACCCAUGAGAAAACUGAAUGAAUCUCAGAGAGGAGCAAACUAUGUCAAAAGUCACAUAAUUGGAUAGUGAGAUUAUGGUGUUUGUACUGAAAUAUGUUUAACUUCAGAGCUCAUGCUCUGAACACAUACUAUACUGCUCAUUUAUUCAUUUAUUCACAUAUAUAUUGUGCAACCACAGUGUGCCAGGCACUGGGCUGAAACAGGAGGAUGAGAGAACCACUCCCUGCAUUCUUGGCAUGAAACUUACAGUAUAGCUGUGAAUGAGACUUAUUUAUGAAAUAAUCACAUAAAUGUAUAACUGUGAACUAUGAAAAGCAAUAUUAAGGAAUGGAUCACUACAGGAUUAUGCGUAGGUACUAGGGUAAGUAUAUACCUAUUAGAAGGAAACUAUGAACUAUAAUAAGUGAUAUUAAGGAAAGUUUAGAGAGUCAGAAAACUUGAUAUAAUUUUAGGGAGUCAAGGAGAACUUCCCGAAGAAAGGGGCACAUGCUUUCAGAUCUGAAGGAUUAACAUGAUAGCUAAGCAGAGAGAACUUGCUGGGUAGGGAAAGGCUAGCAGGUACAAGGGCCCCGAGGUAGGAGACAGCUUGACAUGUUGCUGAUUCUGUGAAUACUUAUUGAGGCAUAGUGUAGCUACUGGUUUGUCACUUUUGUUGUGUUUCAUAUUCCUCCAUUGAACGUAACAUUUUUUACUGUUUCACUAAUGAAUUGAUGUGAAGAUAUUCUAUUUUAUGCAGUUUUGAUUUGUUUGUUUUCUGCUAAUUUUAUCUGACAAAUUUAAAGUUUUUAGGGGAAUAAGGGCUACAUCUGUCAUUGCUGUAUCACAGUUUCUAAGAUGGCAUGCAGUUUAGGUACUUAAGUGCAUUUUUAUAGUAAAGAAUAAGAAUAAUAAUAAAUGUCAAUUCAGAGACUAAUAGAAUUUAGUUGCUUUUAGCUGAUAUGCUCAAUUAAGAAUUGACACUGUCUGUAAAAAUCUUAUCUUUAUAUAUAAUAUGAGCUAGGAAAUAGAUUCAUUUCUAAUUUUUGCUAAGUGAAACAUUUUAAUAUUCCUUGAAACUAAAUGGAAAAUUUUCCAAAGUAAUGCUUGGCAGUUUGGCAUGUGGAGAAAAAAAAUCUUUCCUCUAGAGCAGCUUUUCCAGGGAACAGAUUAGAAUUAAUUAGGGGAUGUUUUACUAAUGGAAUAUUUUUCUUCCCAUUAAUGUCACUGUCCUUCAUGCCUGAGGAUGGCAUUAUUGGCAAUGAUUGCUCUUAUGUGUGAGAGACUAUAUAGACAGACAGGCCAUUGCAUAGAAUUCUAUUUGUCACACAACCUGAGACCACUGUCUUUAGUUUCAAAGCCUGAAGCUGUUUGUCUGGUCUGGCAUUGUUUGGGACCUUACCUGCUAAAACUGUAAUUGGCCCAGAGUCUUUUCUUGAAUUCCACCCAAAUUCUUUCCCUGUGACAUAAAAUCAUUCUUAAAUAACUUUUUAGGCAAUAAAGCCUCCUCAGAUUCAAUCCCCAUGCUAUCUGUGGUGGGGAACACUAGGAUAUUGAGCCUUUAAAAACAUGCACCAUAUCUUAUUUGUCUUUGUAUUUCUAAGAUGUAGCAUAGUGAUUGGCUGAUAGGAGACAAUAAGUAUUUGCUAAAUAUGUAAUUAAUUGAAUGAAUGGUGAUCAACUAAAGGUGGGUUCCAGAUUACAAUUUUUGAUAACCAGCUCAAAUUUCCUUGCUACCUUGGACAUUAAUGAUCAUAGAUUUAAAACUAUGAAUAACUACAAUGAGAAUGCUCGUACGAUCUCUGUACAAUCUGUAUUGGUUAUCUAAUUUUUUUUUUUUGAGAUAGUGUCUCGCUCUGUCACCCAGGGUGGGGUACAGUGGCCCAUUUUUGGCUCACUGCAACCUUCGCCUCCCAGAUUCAAGUGAGUCUCCUGCCUCGGCCUCCCAAGUAGCUGGGACUACAGGUAUCCGCCACCACGCCCAGCUAAUUUUUGUAUUUUUUAGUAGAGACCGGGUUUCACCAUGUUGCUCAGGCUGGUCUUGAACUUGUGACCUCAAAUGAUCCACCCACCUCAGCCUCCCAAAGUGCUGGGAUUACAGGUGUGAACCACCAUGCCUGGCCAUGGUUAUUAUUCUGAAUAAUGAAUUACCUCAAAAUUAAUUAACAUUUAUUACCACAUAUGCUUUCUAAGAGUCAGGAAUCAGAGAGCAACUUAGCUGGGUGGUUCUGGUACAGGUCUCUCCUGAGGUAGCAGUCAAGCUGUAUGCUGGGGCUAUCAUCUGAAGCAUGAAUAGAGAUGGAAGAUCUGCUUCCAAAGGCUGUUGACAGGUGACACCAUCAUGUGAGCCUCUCUGUAGGGCAGUUUAAUUGUCCUCCUGACAUGGUGGCUGGCUUCCCUAUAGCAAGUGAUCAAAGAGAGAAAGCAAAAAUUAAGCUGCAUGGUCUUUUAUGACCUAGUUCCAAAGUUGCACACCAUACUUCCUUCCCCUCUAUUUUGUUCCUUAGAAGCUGGUCACUGAGUCAAACCUGCACUCAGGAAGAAGGUAGUUUUCACCUUUUCUGAAAAGAGGAAUAGCAAAGAAUUUGUAGAGAUUUGAAAACACUAAAAUACCUAAACAUUGAAACUCCCCCAGAGUAUUUACAUGAAUUGCAUGUUUUCUAAAGUAGUGCAAUGUAUCACAAUGUUCAAUUUGUCAAUAAGAAGUGCUUUUAGACAAAGUGCUUUUCCUGGAAAUUAGCUAACUGUCUUAAAGUAUAAAUAAUGUCAUUUUGAAAAAAAACAAAAAUCCUUGUAACCAUGAAAACAAGAAUCACCAGUACUUGAAGAAUCCAAAUAAUGACCUAAUUUUGUUUUUAUUUUCUUUUUAUUCCUCUGAAGUAGAUUCAACAAAUUCAAGUAAAGAACAUUAUGUGCAUCUACUUUGUGCCAAUUACUAUGUCAUGUGCUCUGGGAAGGGGAUACACUUAUGCAGAGGUGACAAAGAUAUAAUCUGUCCCAGAGAAGCUGAGAGUAUAACAGAGAUGAUGGACACAUACACAAAACUUAAUAUGAUAUGAAGCUCACUGUAUUGAGUUUUGUGAGAGAGCUACAGAGGAGGUGUUAUGGGGGCACAAGGAGAAGAAAGUUAAUUAACAUUGAAAGAUGAGAAGACAUCUUGGAAGAACUUGAAUUGGGCCUUGGAAGAAGAACAGCCAUUCAAAUAGAUAGAAUUGUGGUAGCAAAGGCAUAGAGGUAGGAAAGUAUAGAUCUCCAGGGACAGUAGUCAUGGGGUUGGGGCACUGUUGGAAUUUAAGGUUGGAAGGAUAUAUUGGAGCCCCUUGAAUACGGUAACAAGGCACACCUUGGGCAGUGGAGAGUUAUCAGAGUGUUUGAAAAGGAGGGUUAUUGAGUAAAUAAAUAGACUGGUACUUUAGGAAUUUUAAAAUGUGGAUCAUUGUACUACUAAUAACUAUUUAUUUUAUAUUUACUAUCUACUAAGUAAUUUACAUGUAUUUUCUUGUACUGACUGUAAACCUUCUGGGUGUGGGUGUUUUAAGUGCCAUUUUACUGAUAAAGAAACUGAGGCUUAAAUAGUUGAAAUAAGUCACCCUGUUAGUGAGUGGCAGAAUGACAAGUCAGAUCUAGGGUUGUCUAACUCCAAAGAUAAUAUAAAAUAAUGUAUCUCUCUUUUCCCUUAUGCAUAAAAUAUGGGAGCAUAUUAAAUCAUACACAUAGAUUGUCAAAAAAUACUUUGGGAAACUGAUUAUAAUAUCAAAUAAUUCAGUGCUGCUGUCUCUUACACUUUUAUCCCUAUCUGUAAAACAAACUACAAAUUGAGAGAGUACAUUCCAUAGCUUGGGAAAAAACCCAAUUGUGUUGUACCUAAACUAAUCAUCUUAAGGCAGUAGUUCAGAAGAACAGUACUACUAUAAGCCUCAGAAAGAGGAAACUACCUGGGUAUGGCGGGUGGGAGCGGAGAGAGGAUCCGAAAAAAAUACCUAUCGAGUUCUAUGCUUAUUACUGGGGUGAUGAAAUUAUCUGUACAACAAAUCUCUGUGACAUGCACUUUAUAUAUAAUACAAACCUGCACAAAAACCUAAAAUAAAAGUUAAAAAAAAUGACAAUCAAAGAAAAAAAGAAAAAAAAAGAAAAUACCUGGCUGGAUCUACCCUCUAACAUUUUUAGGACUCAGGGCAAGACAAAUGAAAGCCUACAUACUAUGUGUCUAAAUAUUAAACAUUAUAAAUAGGCUAACAAAUGGUUAAGUAAAAUAUGCUUUGUCUUUCUACCUUGACAAAUAAAUGUUGAUAAUGACAAAAUUGAAAAAUAUAUGGAAAGCUGUCAUUCUUGAAGUCAACAAAAUGUCCAUGAUGACUGUAAUCAUUAUUGUGUACAUCUGAAUAUUCUGUUGUGGGGUUGGUGAUGUUUCCAUGAGUAAUAAAAUUAGGUCAUACAUAAUUAAUAUAUUAUUACUUAAUCUGUAAAAUUUAUUUUUGCUUUCAUUUCUGCAAUUCCCUAAUUAUGUUGUUAUAAUGACAGUUUUCAUAUAACGUGUCUUCUAUUGACAGUAAUGAUCUAAAUAUUAGAUUCUAAAGUAUUAAAAAUGAAGUGUAAUAUUAAAGUACACACAAUUUGAAUUUAUUUUCAUCAAAAAUGUAAAGUAAAAAUAAAAAUCCAAAACUAAAGGUUAGCUUUUGUGCUACUAAAAGUUUUCUUCUAAAAUCUUCAGUUUUCUGGGAAAAAAGGCAAAAUUCAAAGUAUAACUAAUGAAUAUAACAUUCAAAUAAUUAUUUAAAUGAAACAAAUUAUAUUUUUUGAAAAUUUAAAUCACAUUAAAUAUUUUUAUAAAAAUAAAACUGGUAGUAAUUCUAGUGUUCAAUGGUGAUCCAAUUACCAAAGAAUCCCUAGCACACUAGUCACUACUAGACCUGCAUAUAUUUAACUUUAAGGGCCAUAGGAAUUGUUUAAUAUUACAAGAUGUUCUUUGGCCACGAUAUGCAACUUUUGGGGUUAUCAAGGUAAUAGGUGAGUACUUCUGGAGCAUCGAAUUAGAACAUGAAAAGAAGUAGCAAAAUGGAAGCUUGGCACUCCUGGGAAAUGAUAUCUCAUUAUCCCUUGCAUUCGUGCUGAGAGGAAAGACUUGACAAGUUAAUUAAUUUGUCUUUUUCUUAACUGAGUGCUUCUGCUGCUCAACUCCUCCCUGCUCUCUAAAGAAGUGUCCUUCUCUGAUAUGGGCAGCAUCACAAUCCAGCCUCAAAAGAAGCCACCUUGGGCUUCCAAGACACAAAGCAGGGGAUAUGGAGAGGUGUCUGCACUAGAGUCUGGAUGGUGCUACUGACAACAGUGAGUGUUCAGGGUGACUGCUAGUGCUGUGCAGUGCUGAGCGCCACAUUCCAUGGGACCACGUGUCCUUUAAUAAACAUAUUCAGCGUGCGCUUAUGGAACUCAUGGCUUCUAAAGCACAAGGCGUAUGUUUCAAGCAUAGUGCUAUCCCUGAGCAGCAUUUGUAAGCCUCCAGUCUGCAACAGUGGGAUUACCUACCAGGCUCAGCUGAUGGACCGGGAUGAUAUUGGAAGAGAGGCUGCCAGCCUGAAGACUUACCUGGAAACAUUUUCUCGUUGGUCUGGUUUUAAUAAAAUCACCAGAUUCCACUAGAAGGAAACCAAAGAUUACAAAGGUCCAAAUUAAUAUAUGACAAAGUAGAAACGGAAACUGGGAGGAAAUGAGGUGAAACACAGGGGAUGAUGUAUUGGAAAUAGGGAAUGAAAACCGUACAGAGUAGAAACACCUGAAAGCAGUUCUGGAAACUCCACAUGCUCCUGCUGUACCAAGACCUGGUCCUAUGUGUGCUGACCUUGUUCUUCUGCUCACAUCUGCCACAUCUGCAAAUGUGGCAACAUUUUAGCUGUUUUCUAUUAACACUGAAGUACUCUGAGAGCUUGGAAAUUUUCAAGUGCAAAAUCAGGUCCAGAGAACAGUAAAAAAAAAAAAAAAAAAAAAAGCUUGACUGAACUGCCACUCACAUCUUCCCUAUACUGUGCAGAAGCAAAGAGCUCAAUACUGAUUUUGGUUUUGUGGUUGAAGGCAACUGCUAUGAAACUUCUUAAGUGGUUCAUAGUUGUCCAUAUUUUAUCCUUAUGAUUGAAACAAUAUUUCCUGCUUUCCCCAGAGUAAUAAUUUUAAAGGUGGGGUCUCUAACCUCGGGUAUAGCCUGGCCUCCACAGUGUUACACUGUUCCCAAAAUGACAGGGGAUACAAAACAGAUGGGUCACACUGCAGGCUGCAGAAGUGGGAUUUUGUUCCUGAAGACAAACCCCACACUACAGGAAAGGCCCAGCGCUAUCUCUGAGUCUUGAUAGGUUUGGAAUGACUUUAAAGUUAUUAAUCAAGAAGUGAAUAGGUGGAAACUUGGGAACAUGUCCUUCUCUGUGGUUAACAGUGGGAACAGCAAGGCUAAUUGCUUUAAGUCUAAAUAAUCAGAAGCUGUAAACUCUGUCACCCAAACUUCCAGUUUAUGUCACUGGCUUUCUGGAGGCUGCAUUACAGUGUUGUGGUGGUGAAAUUAUUAUUAAUUAAUGACCAUAGUAUUAAUAACACUAUAUACUGUGAACUUAUUUUAUAGUAAUACAUCUCCUCAGUGCUCAAUAAAUACUUGUUGAAUAAAUACUUUCUCAUUAGUUGGUUCAACAAAUGCCCAUUGAAUACCUGUUAUGAAAAAGGCACUGGGUACUGAUCCAAAAAUGAAUUUGUUUUAGCCAGAGUCUUCCAAGAGAUUAGAGUUUUACAGAUAUUAUCCUGAUGAAUGAACAACCCAGAAAGGCAUCCUCCUUUCAGUUUGAUGAUGCUUUUUUUUUCACUUUUUAUAUAAAAGAUUUUGAAUUUGCUAUUUUGAAAAAUCCAGUAGAGGUUUCAGAGGAUGUAUUUGAAACUUGUAUUUUUUUAAAUCUAUGUCUGACUGUUAAGGAAAUUGUACUUUUUUCCAAGUUACUCUAUUACCUAUAAUACAACCAGAAAUAAAAUGUUAAAAACUCAAGCUCAUGCAUACCCAAGGAUGACAAAAAAAAUUCUGCAUGUAUAAGAACACUUUACAUUGCAUUUUGUAACAACUUGCAAAGAAGAUAAAUAAUAUGUAUGACUCCAGAUUGCAGUAAACAGACUCCCACUUAGCUUAGCUUUUAAGUUAUGCAACUUCCUCACUGAUGACUUAGAAAAAAAUAAAGAGGCAGCAAAUAGUCAAUAAAGAGUAAGGCAGGAAGCAUGUGCUGACUCUGAGUCCCAGGAGGGCUCACCAUGUCCGGUGCCACUAGGGAAACAAAUCUCUAAGGCAGUUGAAAUUUUCCUGCUUCUCACAUAAUCCCAAGCAGAGCACAAGGCAGUGGCUUAAAUCUGCAGGUUUAAAGGAGCACAGAGAAAGAGAAAUAAGAGAAUGAAAUCUGUACCCUAAGAGAGUGAAGGAGGGUCACUCAUUUGUUUACAGGCAGUGUUCCCCCACCCCCUUCUCUAGACAGCAAGGAAUUUGGAGCCUCUGUCAACUCUCAGGCAAAGAUCCUUUGAUCAAUUCACGUAGGGCCUGAUAACGCAUGGACACUGUGGGAGAUUAAAAGAAGAUAGUAAUAUUAAUAUAAAGAUCAUGGCAAUGAUAACAACAUGCCACCAUUUAGUGUCUUUGUGUUUCCCAAGAGUUAACACUAUACAUGCAUCAACUCAUUUAAUACAACAUGAUGAAAUAGUCUCAUUUUACUGAGGGAUUAAAAAUAAUAAACUGAUGGCUGAGUAUGUUGGCUCACACCUGUAAUCUCAGCACUUUGGGAGGCCGAGGUGGGCAGAUCACAAGGUCAGGAGUUCGAGACCAGCCUGACCAACAUGAUGAAACCCCAUCUCUACUAAACAUACAAAAAUUAGCUGGGUAUCGUGGCAGGUAUCUGUAAUCCCAAAUGCUCAGGAGGCUGAGGCAUGAGAACCACUUGAACCCAGGAGGGUGGAGUUGCAGUGAGCCGAGCUUGUGCCACUGCACUCCAGCCUACAUGACAGAGUGAGACCCUGUCUCAAAAUAAUAAUAAUAAUGAACUGAGACUCAGAAAAGAUGUUUGUUCAGGGUUACAAAGCUCAGACAGGACAGGGCAGCAUUGGAAACCAAAAUUGGUCUGACUCCUAGGCUCAUGCUGUAAAUCACGGUGCAAGGCUUCUACUAUCUAUGUUUUUCCUAAAAGAAUGUAUAAAUGAAAAGAUGGUUAACAUAUUAAGCAAAAUAUGUUAAACGUCAAAUGAACUGUAUAAACGAUAAAUGCUGGAGAGUUGAGGUGGCAAAGAACUCAUGCCCGAGGUGAUCUGGGAAGGCCUCUUGAACAAGGUGGAAUUAUAGCUGGUUUUUGAAGAAUCCGAAAGUGCUUAGAUUGAAAGGUGAGACAUGUACAGGAAUGGUUUCUAAGAUGUCAUAUUUUAUCUCUGUCCUCAUCUUGACUGGCACUAAUGAACAUCAAAGAUUUCAACCUAAAUACAUUGAGUGCCCAGUAUGUGAAGGGCCUUAUUUAUGUUGUUUUAAAGCUUUUUAACAUACUUUAAAGAAGGGACUGGUUAAUCUCCACUGUCUAGAUCCAUUAGACCCGGAGCCGGAUGGCCCCAGGGGCCUUUGGGAAUGGCGUGGUGGGACAGUCUCCACUUUUGCACAUACCCAAGAAAAGAAUGGUCCUUUGGGAAUUUUGCAGACCUACAAUCUGGAGAUAAUGUACUUCUGAUCAUAAUUCAAGUGCCCCCAGAUAUAGGGUUGCCAGAUUUAGCAAAUAAAAAUAUAAAAUGCUCAGUUAAAUUUGAAUUUCAGAUAAACAAUGAAUUAUCUUUCAGUACAAGUAUGUUUCAAAUAUUCCAUGGGACAUACUUAUAACUUUUAAAAACUUAUUUGUUAUUUAUCUGAAAUUCAAAUUUGACUGGGCUUUUACAUUUUAUUUGGCAACCUACCCAGUCAGGAAUUGGAGGGAAAAUUUUGAGAUUUGAAUUUUUUGGCAUACAUAAAUACUCUUCUAUGUGAAGACCUCAAAUAAACUAAAAAACAAAAAGAAAAAGUGUCAGUAUUAUACAUUCCCAUAAAAUAUGCUCCAUUUUAAAAUGAGACCAAUGGGGCAGGAAGUUACCUCACAAAAGUAAUUUUGUGGAAAUAAUAUAAAAAUCUCUGAGUUUUUAUACUUUAUUUAUUCAAGAAAUUCUGGCCUUAAAAUAGUAGUCAGUUGACCCAAGUAAGUCACUUGCUCUGCAUCAAGAUAAAAAUGCAUUUCAUGCUGUGUACGCUGAGGAUAAAAAAAGACAUGCUGAAAACUGGAUUUCCAAGUAGUGCCCCUAUUAAAGAUGACAAUUAAGUGGGGUUCACCGAGGAUGCAUGGUGCCUUAGGAUUGAAUUAUAAGAAUGAUGAUUGUUUUUGGAGUUGGAGUCAAAUAUCAGCCUUUAAACCAAGUCAAAGCCAGGGUUACAGCUGCGUUACAGCUGCCUUCUGUCACUGACACUGCUGUGGAAAAAUUCAAAAGGCACACCAAACGUUUUUUCUAGUGCAUUUUUCAAAGCAACUUGGAAUUAGUACAAGUACCUCGACGCAGAAAGCAAAUGUAUUUACCUAUGUAAUAUCAAGCUUGCCUGGAAUCAUUUAGUAGGAAAAAGUAUUCUGCAGAGAAAUGUACUUUGAGAGAAUGCAAAGCAUGAAAGGUAAAUUGGAGUCUUGAAGGGGGGAUUUUAAAUCACAUUUAGACAUAAAUCCUUUCAGGUCAUGAUUCCCAUAGAUUACCAGCAUCUGCUAAGCCUAGAUAGUUCAUAAUCACUAAAAUUGUCGUAAUCUUCCUAUGGAAGGUUUACCAAAGAAGUACUGAAUUACACUGGGUUAAUACUUUUAAGGAUGAAUGGUCAAGACGAUGAUGCUAAAUUAAUGCAGUGGCUACAUAGUAAAAUCUAAUACUAAUAACAUAUCUGAACGAAGCUGUGGUUUCAAAAGGCGUUCACUCCAUCAGGGUAAUGUAUUCUCAGGUAUAUGAUCAACUAGAAAGUUGCCAACCAUUAUUCACCUUCACCUACUCCUACAAGCUUCUCUGUCCUGUCUUAUUCUUUUCUACUGUCAAAAAGAGAGAAGGACUUAAAGGUUGGGUCUGUAAAAUAGGAAACCAUAGAGCAAAAACACAGAUAACACAGUCAAGGAAGAUGCUCGAAUAAAUUAUCGGUGGACAGUGUUCUCUGGAUUGAAGCAUGGAAUCUAAAUAUGGUGUCUCAUAGAGUCUACUGACAUACCACGCUAUAAGUGGAAACAGUGCAGGGCAGCAUCUAGUGCUGUGUGAACUGUAUCAACAGCACCGUGGAGUGACAGUCACCAUGUCCUAUUAUAUUUUUGGUUAUUUAGAUGGACAGUGCAUUUGCGCUUGUGCAGUUACUUUUAGUAAAUGCACAGGAGUGGCAUUCUCACUUUCCUUCACUGCAUUUGCAAGGAUCAAGGGAAAUAUUUCCAGUGACAUGGAGCUAGUAAAAAUUGAUCAAUUGUGAAAUAGCUAAGCAAAUACUUGUUAUACUUUAAUAGGAACAGCAGUGUAACAUGUAAUGAGCACUGAGCAAAGUAUGUUGGAUGCGCUUAUGCAUCCACUGAAUUCGAACAUAUUGGUCUGCUUCUUCAUUCCACAUCCCCACCAUCCUGCUCUCACACUCCCUGGUCUCCAGUCAUAUUCCUAAUUCUCUGAAUACUUUGCUUCAUGGCCUCUUACAUACCUAUUUGCUUGUGCACCUCCUCCUGCCCCUGGUGGAAUUACCCCUGCCCUUUGUCUCCUGGUGAACCUUUGCUUUUUCAAGUCUCAAUUCAAAAGUCACCCUGACUUCUACUCCCCAGUGUCCUACCCAGAGUUGGAUGCCCCUGCACCGUGUUGCUCCAGCCCUGAAUUCACACCCUCUGUGAGAAAACACAUUACGUUGGCUUCUAAUCAGUUGCUUCCCUGCUUUCUUCUCUCAAUGGGCUGCACGCUUCCUGAGAACAGGGACUGAGUCUCUUUCUGCUUUUCAUUUUCAGAACAGAGUGUCUGUAAUACACAGCAUACCUAAAUGAUCCAUAAGCAUUUUAUUACAAGUAAUCUGGAGUGCACCAUGGCCUGGACACUCUGGGGCAGUAUGGAUAAAUAGAAUACCAGGACCAGACAUACCCAUGUAAAACUUCCAAAAUGUCUACAUGUAAAGCUACAAAUUUAAUGGUACCAACAAUAAAAAUUGGUGCAAUCAAGAGAAGUGAAGUAAAAUUCUCUGGGAAGAAUUGAGGAAAGCCUUAUGAGAAAGGUGAAAUUUGAGGUGGGACUUAAGAGAGGCAUUAAAAUGGAAGAAAGCAGUGGCUUCCUCUUCCUGGGAGUUCAUCAGGGCCAUAGACUUUAGGGCAGAAAAGUCAAACUACAGACUGAAAAGAAAAGGCCAAGUAUGAAUGGAGGGUUUAGGUUGAGGAGUAGGCUAAGAUCUUCCUGGUUCUUCCCUCUGUGCAACACUGAGAAUCUUUUUCCUGUGUCCAAUUUUACAUCUUCUUCUUCUGGUUUAAGCAUGCCUAAAAGAGAUUACCAACUACCAACUUCUGAAGACACAGUUUGUGUAGUUCCUGUGGACUGGGACAUGUGACUCUGCAAAUAUGAUACUAAAUACUCUAUUUUUUUUUUAAGCAAAUUGAGUAUGUAACUCUGUCUCAAAAUAUGCAGUACAUGUCUCAGCCUUAAACUUGUUCCCCUGUGCUUUUAGAUAAUAAUUUUUUGAAAUGUGUUUGGAAGUCUUUGGGGGCCUAAGUUUAGAAAGCUAGAAAGACAUUCUCAUUGCCUUUGUUGUUCCAAUCUGUUGUUCUGUAAUUUCUGGACUUGGAUCUAUCAUUUGACUGAAAAGGAUAAAAGGUCCAAGAGUGAAAAGAAAUGGGUUAAAGAGAGGGAACAACCAGCCAAAGCAGUGGCAGCCAGCACCCGAGGGGGGUGGCUGCAGCUGGGCUCUGCCCAGCUGCAGGUGUGGAGGAGGAAGUGCAGGAACGAGCCCAGGACCCAUUUCCAGGUGGCAGCAGGGUUCAGUGGGCUUAAUUAACCGGUGAACUGCUCAUGAGGUCGGUCUGUCUCUACCUUUCUACACCACACUGAACAAGCCACUGACCAUUUCCUGCCUCGGAUUUCCUCAGCCCCAAAGAGGGGACAACAAUGUGUAUUCGUCAGAGAAAUUACUGGCCACUGUCUCAUUCAGAAGCUGCCCCUAGAAGUGUUAGUAAAGACUUUUAAAAACAUGAAACAAAGCAGAGAAUUAAAAAUAACAGGAAGUGGAAGAGAGAGCACACUAUGAUCUGAAAUCUUCUGUGUUAUAUGCUGGUGUUAAAGAGGUCGUGAGGCCUUGAUGAAGAUUUGUUACUUGGAAGGAUGUCAGUGCUGGGGACCUGCUCUCUGUGAACCCAGCAACCUGCCCCAGCAUUUCAAGGGGCAUACAGUCCACUCAGAUGAUUUAUUUCUGAGUUGGAAUUACCCCAUUCCCCAGCCCACCCUCUUUUCAACUUUGUACAAAUGUAAGUGGCCAAUUCACUUUACUACACAAAUGACUCAUGAUUUCAUGAGCUGCAAGCAGCAGUUUCUUAAGCAGCUUUCCCAUAUUCCUAGUGCAAGAAAUGGACACACAGACAUCUCUUAUGGGCUAGAUCUUUUUAAUUUGUGAAGCAAAGAAAGUGAGGGAACCACUGGACCCAAUCUCAAGUAUCCAAGGUCAACUAGACGAGGCACAUGGCCAAUUUCCAAAGACACAUGGUUCUUUCCUAAUCCUCAGCCUCUACUUCCUCACUGGAUCUGAGUUCAAAUCUCAGAAAGGUCAGAGCAUGUGCAUUUUUGGCAUUUUUAAACAAAUGGAUGCAAUUAAGAACUUGAGGAAAGGGUGACUUUCUAUAGUUUUCAGCAUACAUCAGCUACUUGACAACUUCUACUAAAAUAGAGCUGCUUUCAGAGGGUAAUGUGAGUAGCCAAUCACUGCCACUCAGGACAAAAAUGUUGGCCAAUGACCUAGAAGUAAGUGUGUGGUGUAUUUCGCAUGACUAUAAGUGCUUCUCAUUAGGAAAAUAAUGGCAUCAGUUCCUGGAGUUUUCUUGGUUAUUUAAACCUCCUGCUUUGGAGUUGAGUUCAUGGUUUACCAACAUCAGCAAGUGUUUCCUAUUUUGUUGUACAUGAUCACCAAAGGAAUAGGAGGCAAUAAAGGAAAUGAGAACUAAAGGUUCUAGAGAGAUUACAUUCUUUAUCACAUUUAAUCUUUAUAAGAACCCCCAAAAGUUGGUGUUCUUUCCUCCAUCUUACAGAUGUUUUGAAAACUGAAGCUCUGAAAAGUUACGUAACUUGGAUCUACAGAGCUCUAAGAGGACGUGCUAAGAUUUGAAUCCAGAAUUUCGUGACUCAAAAACGUUUUCUCCACAAUAUCAGUUUACCAGAAUAACCUAGGCAUGGCCUCAAAAGACCUAUAUUAGAAAUUAGCUAUAUCCUAGUUCUAAGGAAGUAUUCAUUUUUUAUUAUUCAACUGUUAAAACUGCACAUAUAUUAUAUUCCAUAGAAAUUCUGAGCAUCAAUAAUAGGAGAUACUUUCACUAUUUGUAUAUAUGUAUAUGUAUAUUUGUGUAUAUAUACAUACAAAAUAUAUUUUACAAUUGUCUCUUUGUUCCAAGAGUGGGAAGGAAAAUAAUUAGAAUUUGUAGUUGGGCAUUUGUGUCCACUUUAACCUGAUCCAUUCUGUCUAACUUUUCUUUGCAAGCUCUCAAAUUCAUUGUUAGCCUAUCUGAUCCUGUCGUCUGGAGACUGCCAAGUAUUUCACAUCUUACCCAGGGAACCGACCACUUUUAAGGGAGGGAGGGCACUCUUUACUGACUUUUCCUAAUUUAAAUUCAUUGAAAAUUGUUAAUUUUAAGGGCAAAGACAAGGCAAUGCAUCUGUAAAGAGCUCUGUCACUUUUCUCCAAGUGAUGACUAAUGGUGGGGAACUUAAAACCUUAUCCUUGGUAUCUUUUGGAGUCCAGACAAUUCAGUGGUCUCCUGGGAUGAGUAAAUAUCAGCCCGUUCCCAGGAAGAUUAACUAGUAAGAUGAUGUAGGAAAAGCUGCUACUUUUUAGAGGGCUAUACUUAAACUGCCAUCUACACUUCUUAAGGCAGAAUCUCAGAUAGUUUACUUCCAUAUGGGAUGCUAUGAUUUCUAGAAAGAAAGGAUAUUUUAUACAGUUAUAAGAGUAACAGUGGUUUCUUUCCAAGAUGUUAAAUUUGGUCUCAAGGUUAGUGUUUGUUAAUGUAAUGUAAUUACUGGUCUUUAAAAGAUCAUAAAGUAGAGUAGAAUUAGGAGACCUGAAUUAGGGCUCUCCAUUACUGGGCGUAUAGUUGUAGGUAAAUUCCCAGUUUCUUUACCUGUUGUGCAGGUAGCAAUACCUAUCCAUAUUCCCUCAUAGCCUCACAUUUUUAAAAUAGGAAGAAUGCUGAAGUACUUUGAAAGUUCUAAGAGCUCCAAUGGGGUCCUGUAGCACAUGGGCUUUGUAGUCAGAAAGCCCCAAAUUCAAAACUUAGCUUUUCUACUCUUUUCCUGUGUGGGUCAGUUUUCUAAACUCUCUGUAUCUUGGUCACCUCACCUGUAAAAUAGGCUAAAAAUAGUUCCUACCACAUAUGAUACUUGUGAGGACCAGAUGGGCUCUUGGUAUGCUUGAGUUGAAAAGGCUCAUAGAGUUUAUGUUACCCAUUCCUCCUAAUUGUAAGAUGAGGAAACCGAGGCCCUGGCUGGUAGAGUGUCUUACCCAAGUUCAUUCAUCAAUAAUUUUUGAGUUAUACCAAGCAAUUUGCCUGCAGAGAUUCAAUGUUGCUUAAAUUACCAUGUUGCCUCAAUUCUUAGGAAGACUUCUUUUUAAUUGAGAGGUCUUCUUGCUCCUUUAUGUCAGAAGGAAUGGUCACAUUGCUGACUUUUUCUUGUUUAUGGACUGAUGACUCAUUUAUGAGUUAUCUAAACGUCUUGUUCCUUCUUUCUCUCUUCUGCCGUCUCUAUCAUGGGACUAUUUUCUUUCUGCUAGCACUUCUACUAGAGAUUGUGAAAGGGUGGUGACAGUGAAUUAACUCCUUGUUAGCAGCCUUGUCUCUUGAGAGGAGGCUCACCCACUGCUGCUGACUGAUAAGAUGAUGACAAUCUCUGCUUCCUAAAAAAUCUUCUCUACUAUUAAGUUGGUGCAUAAGUCAUUGCAGUUUUUGCCAUUACUUUGCCUUCCAGAUUGCCUCUUGCUUCUCUCUGCUCUACUUGCUCCUUCUUUGCUGGAUCCUCUUCCUGGGUAAACCCUUAAAUGUGUUACAUUCUUUAGGAUCUGUCCUUGUCUGUCUUUGAUUCUGCCUGCUCUUCUCGGUGAUCGCAGACACUCUUGUGUCCUCAGUUACCAUCUAUCUGACACUGGCUCCUAAAUCCAUUAUCUUUAACUUAACUUUCUCACUUAACUGCCAGAUCUCAUUGCCUCUUGAAUAUCUCUGCCUGUUUCCCACAGGUACUUCAAAAAUUGUAUCCACAAAUGAGAUUACGAGUCCCCCUUCCACACACACACACACACACACACACACACACACACACACACACUUUGUCUUCCUUUUAUAGCCUAAAUUAAUCAAGCAUUCUCAGCUCCUUGCCCAAGUUCCAUAUCUAUCCAGUUUUCAAAUCAUUUUUAUUUUAUCUUGAAAUAUCUCUUGAACCCAGCACAUCGCUUUCCUAUUUUACUGAUACAGUUGCGUCAGUUCAGCACUCAUCUUUUUUCACCAUAGCUUCCUAACUUUUCUCUGUGGCCUAGUUCUCUCCAUUCUAUCUAAUCUUCCCUCUGUAUUCUGCCACAGAUAACUUUCAAAACUGAAUUUUAUCUUUGUUGAUCUUCUAUUAGGAAAAAUGUUAGAUCCUCAACUAGUGCUUAAAGACGAAUCCAAACUAUUGUAAUAUAUUAGCAAUUUCCAGGAUUAGAGCUCCAACCCCUUUCCAUCUGCUCCACUAGGUACCCUGUGGGCCCCUGUGAUUCAUUUACAAUAAACUUGUCACAUUUCCUCAAGUACUUGCCUGACAUCAGAUGUGUGACAUCCUCAAAGACGCCCCCAUACCUCUGAUCUUCCCUUCUCUUACAACUACCCCUUGGGCCCCUGCAAGUCAGUAUUUCAUUCUUAUUUUUAUAUUAUGAUAUCUUUUUACAUCUGUCUCACCCAACAGACUUUGAGCUCAUCAAAUUGGAUAACAGGCUUUUCUUUUUUUUUUUUUUUAAUUUCAAAGACCCUAUCACAUUGGACAAUGUCUUCCACUCAAAAGGAAUUCAGUAAAUAGUUGUUGAAGUAAUGUACUUACGACAAUUAUUAAGAUCAGAGGAAUAUUGUUUAUCAUUCAAUGUUUAUAGUUAAAUAUUUGAUUUUUGAUAACCAUUUACUGAAUAAUUCACCUAACACCCCAUAAACUAAUUAACAAAGAGUGUCUUCAUAAAUGGUGUUGAUAUCACAUCAAGAUGCUAACAGUGUAAAAUUAGGAUUUUAAAAAUAUGUAUGUACCUUUAAGGCUUCUGUGACUUUUAGGUUUCUCUAAAGUUUAUUUAACUUUAAUCCACUUAAAUUUCUUUAAAAGUUAACCAUUAUACAUAAGGUAAUCUGACUCCAAAUUUCUGAUUAUUAUAUAAAAUCCAAAGAUAGGUAAGGAUAUAAAUCUAAAUGUAGUCCAAUAAAUGGACAGAAAAAUGUCAGCUUCACAUGUAGUUUAUGGAAGUAGUGCAUAUAUGAAGCCACAGAAAAGGAAGAGACAAAGGAAUUUCAAAUUUUGGAAUUUAUAAUUAACAAUUAUAUUCACAUAUGCUAUAGAGUAAAAUAGUGUGAAAAGUUGAACAAUAUAUCUAUAUAUUGGUUUUAUAAAAGUAUCAUGGUAUGCAGUUAAUUGUUGAACACUAUGCUUAGAGAUAAGAAAAUAUUAAUAAUAUUUAUAGUAACAUUUAUUGGGCACUUACUCUAUGCUCUAUGCUAGGUGCUGUGCUAAGUACAUCAUAUGCAUAAUUUAAUCCCCCCAAUAUCUCUUUGACACAGUUCCUCUUGUUACUCCUGUUUUCCAGAUGAGUAAAUAAUUCUUAGAAAGAGUGAUUGACUUGUCAGAGGACUUAACAAGUUUUAGAGCUGUUUGAACAUAGAUCUGAUGUGUUGUUCUAUAUUAAAUGAAUGAAUACCUUUUAGGUAUCUCAAUUCUAUACUAAUUAGUAAGUAACUGAUAAAUCAUUUGGUAAAUUUCUAUAAACUGUGUUUUGGACAUAUCUAAAAUGAUAAGGCAGGUGGGCACAGUGGCUCAUGCCUGUAAUCCCAGCACUUUGGGAGGCCGAGGUGGGCAGAUCACCUGAGGUCAGGAGUUCCAGACCAGCCUGGCCAACAUGGUGAAACCCCAUCUCUACAAAAAUACAAAAAUUAGCCAGGCGUGGUGUCGGGUGCCUGUAAUCCCAGCUAUUUGAGAGGCUGAGGCAGGAGAAUCGCUUGAACUCAGGAGGUGGAGAUUGCAGUGAGCCAAAAUUGUGCCACUGCACUCACUCCAAACUGGGCGACAGAGUGAGACUCCGUCUUAAAAAAUAAUAAAAAUAAAAUAAAAUAAAAUGGUAAGGCACAUUUUGUAGUCAUUAUUGAGAACAAAAGAAAAGCAAAAUUAACUGAGAAUCUUUGAAGUUAGGUAUUGUUAACUACUGAUUGUCUAAAUCCACCACUUCAGUUUGUUUUAAAGUCUGCUUUUCUAUCAAAAUUUUGAACAUUCACCGUAAAGUAUGCCUCCAGAAAUGACCACUAAUAUAUUAUUAAACUAUUCUUAACUAUUCCAUGCAUAGUGGGAGAUAUUGAGGUCUAUUGCUUGAUAUAAGAAAUUAAACUGUAUUUCUUCUUUCUUUUCCUGCUGGAGGGUAAUUUACAAAAUAAUCGAUAGUUUCGUGGCACUGUUAAAGUGGAAAUGCACUCAAAAUAAUUACAAUUAAAGGAGCCUACAGAUUUUAUAAUGCCCAGGUUAAUUAUCUUCAGAAUAUCUGCCCAAUACAGUAUGUUACAGGAUACCAAUAAAGAAUACAAUUAUUUUUUUCUUGAUACUUUGCUUUUUUGUUUGUUUGUUUGUUUGUUUGUUUGUUUUAGAGAUGGAAUUUCACUCUGUCACCCAGGCUGGAGUGCAGUGGCGCCAAUCUCCGCUCACUGCAACCUCCGUCUCCCAGGUUCAAGCGAUUCUUCUGCCUCAGUAGAGACAGGUUUUUACCAGGUUGGCCAGUCUGGUCUCGAACUCCUGACCUCAAGUGAUCCACCUACCUCGGCCUCCUAAAGUGCUGAGAUUACAGGCGUGAGCCACUGCACCCAGCCUUUCUUGAUAUUUGAUCCCUAGAGUCCAAUGCAUAAGUAGAUGAAGAUGGAGCUGCUUUUAUUAUAAAAUUUGAGGGAUGUGAAGAAGGUACCCUUGUCCCAAAAGACUGCCCCCCCACCCCCCACCCAAAAAAAGUUACAGGUUUUCAAAGUUUUCAAGUCUUUGGUUGCUCUCUGUGAACAAGUAAAUAUCCCUGGGAGCACUAACCCCUUAUGUCUUUUGUCACACACUUAAGUAAUCAAACUGGGAAGAUGACAAAAAUGCAAAUUCUUAGGGGUACUUCAUAGAUUCUGAUUUGAUCAUUCUGGAAGGAGACUGAGAAACUGCAUUUUAACAAGCACUUUGAUGAUUCUGAUGCAGGAGGUCUUCUGGACCACAUUUUGAAAACUCUUAACAGAUAACUGACACAUCGAGUUGUUAACAAACUGCUCCAGGGUUCCUUGAAAAGAAAACAGGUAGUUAACCUAUCUCCUGCCAACAGCAAGCGACCCAAUGGCUUUGUGGACAACUCAUUUCUUGAUAUCAAAAGAAUUCGUGUUGGGGAGAAUCUCUCUGCAGGACAAGGUGGCCUCCAAAUAAACAAUGGACAAAGUCAGAUUAUGUCAGGGACCUUGCCUAUGAGCCAAGCACCCCUGCGAAAGACUAACACUCUGCCAUCCCAUACACAUUCUCCUGGCAAUGGCCUGUUUAACAUGGGCUUAAAGGAGGUAAAGAAGGAGCCAGGAGAGACUCUGUCUUGCAGUAAGCACAUGGAUGGCCAAAUGACCCAAGAGAAUAUUUUUCCUAAUAGGUACGGAGACGACCCUGGAGAACAACUGAUGGAUCCUGAGCUGCAGGAACUGUUCAAUGAACUGACCAACAUAUCUGUGCCUCCCAUGAGUGACCUUGAACUGGAGAACAUGAUCAAUGCCACCAUAAAGCAGGAUGACCCAUUUAACAUUGACUUGGGUCAGCAAAGCCAGAGGAGCACACCUAGGCCCUCCUUACCCAUGGAGAAAAUAGUGAUCAAAAGUGAAUACUCACCGGGCUUGACUCAGGGCCCCUCAGGCUCUCCUCAGCUGAGGCCCCCAUCAGCUGGCCCCGCAUUCUCCAUGGCCAACUCUGCCCUCUCCACUUCGUCUCCAAUCCCUUCAGUCCCUCAGAGCCAGGCUCAGCCUCAGACAGGCUCCGGAGCAAGCCGGGCCUUGCCAAGCUGGCAGGAAGUAUCCCAUGCCCAGCAGCUCAAACAGAUAGCUGCUAAUCGUCAGCAGCAUGCCCGGAUGCAGCAGCACCAGCAGCAGCACCAGCCUACCAACUGGUCAGCCUUGCCCUCUUCUGCUGGACCAUCACCAGGUCCAUUUGGGCAGGAGAAAAUCCCCAGCCCUUCUUUUGGUCAGCAGACAUUCAGCCCACAGAGCUCCCCCAUGCCUGGGGUAGCUGGCGGCAGCGGCCAGUCGAAAGUAAUGGCUAACUACAUGUACAAGGCCGGCCCCUCAGCCCAGGGUGGGCACCUAGAUGUCCUCAUGCAGCAAAAGCCUCAGGAUCUCAGUCGAAGUUUUAUUAACAACCCGCACCCAGCCAUGGAGCCCCGUCAGGGCAACACCAAGCCUUUGUUUCAUUUUAACUCAGAUCAAGCGAACCAGCAGAUGCCUUCUGUUUUGCCUUCCCAGAACAAGCCUUCUCUCCUACACUACACCCAACAGCAACAGCAGCAACAGCAGCAGCAGCAGCAGCAGCAGCAGCAGCAGCAGCAGCAACAGCAGCAGCAGCAGCAACAGCAACAGCAACAGCAACAGCAGAGUUCAAUUUCAGCUCAACAACAGCAACAGCAGCAGAGCUCAAUUUCAGCCCAACAGCAGCAGCAGCAGCAACAACAGCAGCAGCAGCAGCAACAACAACAGCAACAACAGCAGCAGCAGCAGCAGCAACAACCAUCUUCUCAGCCUGCCCAAUCUCUACCAAGCCAGCCUUUGCUAAGGUCACCUUUGCCACUUCAGCAAAAGCUCCUACUUCAGCAAAUGCAGAAUCAGCCCAUUGCAGGAAUGGGAUACCAAGUCUCCCAACAACAGAGACAGGAUCAACACUCUGUGGUAGGCCAGAACACAGGCCCCAGUCCAAGUCCUAACCCCUGCUCAAAUCCAAACACUGGAAGUGGUUACAUGAACUCCCAGCAAUCACUGUUGAAUCAGCAAUUGAUGGGAAAGAAGCAGACUCUACAGAGGCAGAUCAUGGAGCAGAAACAGCAACUUCUUCUCCAGCAGCAGAUGCUGGCUGACGCGGAGAAAAUUGCUCCACAAGAUCAGAUAAACCGACAUUUGUCAAGGCCACCUCCAGAUUAUAAAGACCAAAGAAGAAAUGUGGGCAAUAUGCAACCAACUGCUCAGUAUUCUGGUGGCUCAUCCACAAUAAGCUUAAACUCUAACCAGGCUUUGGCAAACCCAGUUUCAACACACACCAUUUUAACUCCCAAUUCCAGCCUCCUGUCUACUUCUCACGGGACAAGAAUGCCAUCAUUAUCUACAGCAGUUCAGAAUAUGGGGAUGUAUGGAAAUCUGCCUUGUAAUCAACCUAACACAUACAGUGUCACUUCAGGAAUGAAUCAAUUGACCCAACAGAGAAACCCAAAGCAAUUGUUAGCAAAUCAAAACAACCCUAUGAUGCCACGGCCACCUACCUUAGGGCCAAGUAAUAAUAACAAUGUAGCCACUUUUGGAGCUGGAUCUGUUGGUAAUUCACAACAAUUGAGACCAAAUUUAACCCAUAGUAUGGCAAGCAUGCCACCACAGAGAACAUCAAACGUAAUGAUCACAUCCAACACAACUGCACCAAACUGGGCCUCUCAAGAAGGAACAAGCAAACAGCAAGAAGCCCUGACGUCUGCAGGAGUCCGCUUCCCCACAGGUACACCUGCAGCCUAUACCCCAAAUCAGUCACUGCAACAGGCAGUAGGUAGCCAGCAAUUUUCCCAGAGGGCAGUGGCUCCUCCUAACCAGUUAACACCAGCAGUGCAAAUGAGACCCAUGAACCAAAUGAGCCAAACACUAAAUGGGCAAACCAUGGGUCCCCUCAGGGGUCUGAAUCUCAGACCCAAUCAGCUAAGCACACAGAUUUUGCCUAAUUUGAAUCAGUCAGGAACAGGGUUGAAUCAGUCGAGGACGGGCAUCAACCAGCCACCAUCCCUGACGCCCAGCAAUUUUCCUUCACCCAACCAAAGUUCCAGGGCUUUUCAAGGAACUGACCACAGCAGUGACUUAGCUUUUGACUUCCUCAGCCAACAAAAUGAUAACAUGGGCCCUGCCCUAAACAGUGAUGCUGAUUUCAUUGAUUCUUUAUUGAAGACAGAGCCUGGUAAUGAUGACUGGAUGAAAGACAUCAAUCUUGAUGAAAUCUUGGGGAACAAUUCCUAAAGAAGAAAGGGAAGACAAUUUACAAACUCCAAGCACUAAAAGGCAGUAUAUUACAGAAACUCUGUAGAGGCUGAACUGUUGAUGUUCAGGUGGACUACAUGAAGAUAACAUGCUUAAAAAUGGAAAGCAGAAAGUAACUGCAGUGAUGAACAUUUUGGUCCAAAUUCUUGUUUUAAAUCUUACACCUGAAAGUAAAAUAUUGGGAUCACUUUUCCCUGUCUAAACUCCAGGAUACAGUAUCCAAUUUAUCCAAACAGAACUGUGGUGUCAAUGUGUAAUUAAUUGUGUAAAAUAGCCUUCCCAAGUUUCUUUUUCCCUGGAAAAUAAAAAAGGUAAUAGAACUUGUAGUUUAUUUAAACCCCAUGUCAUGAGGAGGUACUAGUUCCAAGCAACAAACUCCUUAAUUUGCUCUAAUAGAUAGGUAUGGUUUAAUCUUUCCAUUGUGUCUUUUCAUUUAAUUUUCCUGAAGCUUGCAGGAUAGAUUGAAAUGUUAUAGGUUUGUUUGGAGUAACCAAACAGUAUGCAAAUUAAGAAAAAGCCAGAGAACCUAGAAAACAUCCAGUGGAUUACAGAAUUUCUUCCCCAUAUUCACUCCUCACUUUUACAAUUUUCCCACAAUCCUCUACUUCAGUGGGAUGCUGUGUCUAGUGAUUAAACAAAAAUAUAGAGCUGUGCAAUUUGAUUUUGGCUUCCACAACGAAUAUCUGAAUCCAUUCCAAAUGAAAUUUUAGAUAUAACAAAGACUUGUCCUAAUCAUACUGAAAUAUUGGUGCACACCUCUCUGCAUUAGAUUUCACUUUUUUAAAAAACCCAGUGGACAUUGCUAUAAAUAAGAUUUAUUUGGCUACAAAUAACCUGGGAUGUUGCUUAUUAUGAUUGAUGCCUGCUGGUUUGUUCCCAAGCUGAGUGAAAUUGAACCUCGUCCUCCCUACUCAUUUUGAUGACUGAGGCUGGUUUAUAAGAAAAGGAAGUUUGGAGAAGAAAACCGAGAUUAGAAAAUAUCAUGUUUUGGUUGGAGAUAAGAACCAGGGAUGGCAAGUACCAGUGUGUACAAAUGUAUUUCACGGAGUUUGAAGGAACGCAUAAUCAAGAGGGAAAACAAUUUGUCCUUCAUUGGACGUAUUAUUUGGAUUUGGGUGAGCAACAAAAUGGAAUGUGGUCUGUUAGGAGCAUUCUGUUUGUUCUUUUGUCCCUGAUGUGAUGAAUCAUUGCCACAUGCUAGAUGGACUCUUCAUAUCCAGGUUUUGUCCCUCAGGGCUGAGCACUGUAUUAAAGAGUUUUUGUUGAGUCAUUUAACCUUAGUGUCCACAUCCAGAUCAGCUGUAAAAUGGGGAAGACGUGUGCUGAUUUGGAAUGAAUGCAAAAUAUCACUAUCAUUUUCCUAAUUACAGAGGAGCAAAGGUUAUCUUCAGCCCUUUCAGUUCUAUGCUCACAUAUUCAAAUAUCAAAUGUAAUUUAGCUGAAGUUAUUUAAUAAUCAAGUCUUUCAAUAUCUGUUCAAAGAAAAAGAACACACUUUGAAAAUUCUGCAAAGCUGUCUCCCAGUCUUUAAAAUGUCUGGAAGCACUCUCCUUCUUUACAAUACCAACAUCACUGGCCCAGAAUCUUCCCUGUGCUAGUUUGUAAAUAUAAAUAAAUUACUUGUUUUGUAAACUUUUGUAAAGAAUAUUUUGGUAGAAAUACUUCAAACAUAUUCUUUGGGUUAUAUUUAUACAUAUGUGAAAUAAAUAUACUAUCAAAAGGUUAUAUUUUAUACAAAAAGUAAAUUGCUACCUUUUGUAUGCUAAUAUGCAAAGUUUUGUAUAAUAUGAUGGUUUAUUUUUAGCUCUACACUUAAACCAUAGGUGGUUGAGUGGGAACUUUUGAAAACUAUCAAGAGGCUUGUUAGACAAAUUUAUAUUCUGAAACCUCAAUAAGAAAGCAUUCCAGGUUUCAAUCCUUGUUUUUUGUCCUGCUCCCAAAUUCUUUUUUAAACCCAUAGUUCUUGUGUCUUAUUUGAUUCUUCUGCUGUGCACAUUGUAUUGGUCCUUGUUGCAUGUAGUCUACUGUGUGUUUUCCGAUUUUAUAAGGCAGCAUUUCUCCAUACAAAAAGAAAAAAAAUGAUGUACAUAUAAACGCUUUUGUUGUAUGGCUCCUCCAUGUUACUGUAUAUAUCUGCCAGCACUUCCCAGUUACACUCCUGUGAGUCAGCUUAUUUUUACCCUAACAUAAAUAGUAUGUUUUGUAGUAGUUAUCAAAUUUAAGAGAUAAAGCAAUCAGAAUGUUUGGAUUUUCUUCUAUCUUAAUGUGAAUUUCAUAAUUAAUGUCUAUUUAUUCAGCUAUUCAUUAAAAUACAGGAUUCUUUGGGAAAA